AUCCUCUCUGACUCCUGAAUCUUCUGCUCCUUCCUCCUCAAGCAGGUUCACCCGUACUUGUCAAAAUGGCUCAACUCCUGAAUAGCAUACUCAGUGUGAUUGACGUAUUCCACAAAUAUGCCAAAGGGAAUGGGGACUGUGCCUUACUAUGCAAGGAAGAGUUGAAACAACUGCUCUUGGCUGAGUUUGGAGACAUCCUCCAGAGACCAAAUGACCCAGAGACUGUGGAAACCAUCUUGAACCUCUUAGAUCAAGACCGAGAUGGACAUAUUGAUUUUCAUGAGUACCUCUUGUUGGUGUUCCAGUUGGUCCAAGCCUGCUAUCAUAAGCUAGACAAUAAGUCACAUGGAGGCAGGACCUCACAGCAAGAAAGGGGGCAGGAAGGAGCACAAGACUGUAAGUUCCCAGGAAACACAGGCAGACAACACAGACAGAGGCACGAGGAAGAAAGGCAGAACUCCCACCACAGUCAGCCUGAGAGACAAGACGGAGAUUCCCACCAUGGUCAGCCUGAGAGACAAGACAGAGAUUCCCACCAUGGUCAGUCUGAGAAACAAGACAGAGAUUCCCACCACAGUCAGCCUGAGAGACAAGACAGAGAUUCUCACCACAAUCAGUCUGAGAGACAAGACAAGGAUUUCAGCUUUGAUCAGUCAGAGAGACAAAGUCAAGACUCCAGCUCUGGUAAAAAAGUGAGUCACAAAUCUACCAGUGGCCAGGCUAAAUGGCAGGGACAUAUCUUUGCCUUAAAUCGGUGUGAAAAACCAAUUCAGGAUUCUCAUUAUGGUCAGUCUGAAAGACAUACACAACAAUCUGAAACACUUGGACAAGCCUCUCACUUUAACCAGACAAAUCAACAGAAAUCAGGCUCUUAUUGUGGACAGUCUGAGAGGCUAGGUCAGGAAUUAGGCUGUGGUCAGACAGACAGACAAGGCCAGAGUUCCCACUACGGUCAGACGGACAGACAAGACCAGAGUUAUCAUUAUGGUCAGACAGACAGACAAGGCCAGAGUUCCCACUACAGUCAGACGGACAGACAAGGCCAGAGUUCCCACUACAGUCAGCCAGACAGACAAGGUCAGAGUUCCCACUAUGGUCAAAUGGACAGAAAAGGCCAGUGUUAUCAUUAUGAUCAGACAAACAGACAAGGCCAGGGUUCCCACUACAGUCAACCAAACAGACAAGGUCAGAGUUCCCACUAUGGUCAGCCAGACACACAAGAUCAGAGUUCUCACUAUGGUCAGACAGACAGACAAGACCAAAGUUCUCACUAUGGUCAGACAGAGAGACAAGGCCAGAGUUCCCACUACAGUCAGAUGGACCGACAAGGCCAGGGUUCUCACUACGGUCAGACAGACAGACAAGGCCAGAGUUCCCACUAUGGUCAGCCAGACAGACAAGGCCAGAAUUCCCACUAUGGUCAGACAGACAGACAAGGCCAGAGUUCCCACUAUGGUCAGACAGACAGACAAGGCCAGAGUUCCCACUACAGUCAGCCAGACAAACAAGGCCAGAGUUCCCACUAUGGUAAGAUAGACAGACAAGACCAGAGUUAUCAUUAUGGUCAGCCAGACGGACAAGGCCAAAGUUCCCACUAUGGUCAGACAGACAGACAAGGCCAGAGUUUCCACUAUGGUCAGCCAGACAGACAAGGCCAGAGUUCCCACUACAGUCAGAUGGACAGACAAGGCCAGAGUUCCCACUAUGGUCAGACAGACAGACAAGGCCAGAGUUCCCACUACGGUCAGACAGACAGACAAGGCCAGAGCUAUCAUUAUGGUCAGACAGACAGACAAGGCCAGAGUUCCCACUAUAUUCAAUCACAGACUGGGGAAAUACAAGGGCAAAAUAAGUACUUCCAAGGGACUGAAGGAACAAGAAAAGCCUCUUAUGUUGAACAAUCAGGAAGAUCAGGGAGGCUAAGUCAACAGACUCCAGGACAGGAAGGGUACCAAAACCAGGGACAGGGAUUCCAGUCUAGGGACUCACAGCAGAACGGCCACCAGGUAUGGGAGCCUGAAGAGGAUAGCCAACAUCACCAACACAAACUCUUAGCACAAAUCCAACAAGAAAGACCACUUUGUCACAAAGGGAGAGACUGGCAAUCAUGCAGUAGUGAGCAGGGCCACAGACAGGCCCAGACCAGGCAGAGUCAUGGUGAGGGGCUGAGCCACUGGGCAGAGGAAGAGCAGGGCCAUCAAACUUGGGAUAGACACAGCCAUGAGAGUCAGGAAGGUCCAUGUGGGACACAGGACAGGCGAACCCAUAAAGAUGAGCAGAACCAUCAGAGACGAGACAGACAAACCCAUGAACAUGAGCAGAGCCAUCAGAGACGAGACAGGCAAACCCAUGAAGACAAGCAGAACCGUCAGAGACGAGACAGGCAAACCCAUGAAGACGAGCAGAACCAUCAGAGAUGAGACAGGCAAACUCAUGAAGAGGAUCAAAACCAUCAGCAACAACAUAAUAGACAAAACUAUGAGGAGAAAGAGAGGUAUCAAGGAUCUCAGAAUCAAAAAUCCCAAGUGACCCACAGAAGCUGUCCUAACAGAGAAAAAUUCCACAUGAAAGAGGAUGACCAGAGCCAAGGCUCACAGAAAAGACACACUGAACCAUCCUUCUAUCCAACCCAGAGCAGUGGGAGGCCCCAAACCAGAGAACAGCGUGGUCACCCUGCCAAGGGAGCUACUGUUCCCAACCCCCCCUAUGACUAUGUGCAAGAGCAGAAAUCCUACCCAUACUAGGCUAUGUGAGCACCAGAGGUAAAGCAACACAAAGCCAAAAAAGAAACCUAUAUGUCGAGUUCACCUUUAAUUCGAUUUAAGAGAUUGAGAAUGUAUUUCUUCCCUCUAUCCUCUGCUGUAUCUCCCUGCAAGGAUGUUUUUGAGUACUAGCAUUCACGUAAGGGCUUUUGGUUCUUUGAGCAGCAAUUCUAGGGUUUUCUGAUUCAGUGAAAUCUAGGUGGUAAAUUGGGUGAAAUAAUCAUAUCUUAAUGUUGAUCAGUUUGGGUAUUUAAAUCAUUUCCUGCUUUGCCCUCUGUGUAGAUGAGACCUGGUUGAAUCAUUGAAAGGUAGAACACUUCUCCCUAAAGUUCAGAAACAGAAAAGAUAUUCUGAAGAUUUACAUUACAUCCAAGGAUUAUACUACAUCUCCACUCCUCAAGGAACCCUAGAUUUGGUGAGCUUUGGCUCCUGUGGAUAAAACAUCAGGAAUUUCAAGCCUCAUAGUCUAGACUAGAAUGAAACUCAGUUCAAGGCUGCUACAAGAGCCGAGAACAUAGAGUGCAUCUCUGAUGUUUACUACAUCUCCCAUGCCAGGCUCUUAUUCCACACCAGAGGGACUGUCCAUUAGUGCCUAUCACUAGAGCUGAAUGGACCCAUUCCAAUUCAAUACCUUUCUAGUUUCUGAUUAUAUAAAAUAAAGAGAAAGUAUAUGUCAUAUGUUUGCAAAUUCCAGGGGAUCAAGACUAUUGAUUCAUAGCUCCUAAGACCUGAAAACUCUUCUCAAGAAAAUCUAUGUGCAGAUUAUGAAUUGUAUUAAAAUAUCUAAUAAAUAAUUGAUGAGCAAUA